GAUCCCCUUACCCGGGCGUCUCGGCUGUCGCGCCCUGGGCCGGGGGAGGGGAGGCUGCAGGAAGCGGCGGAUCCGGCGGCGGCGGCGAGGGCCCGGGUGGGUGGCCGAACUUCUCCCGCCAUGGAGGGAGCAGCGGCCCGGGAGGCCCGGGGGACCGAGACCCCGCGCGCGUCUGCGCCCCCGCCCGCGCCCUCGGAGCCCCCGGCCGCGCCCCGCGCCCGCCCGCGCCUCGUCUUCCGCACGCAGCUGGCGCACGGGAGCCCCACGGGCAAGAUCGAGGGCUUCACCAACGUCCGCGAGCUGUACGCCAAGAUCGCCGAAGCCUUCGGGAUCGCGCCCACCGAGAUUUUAUUCUGCACCCUCAACAGCCACAAAGUGGACAUGCAGAAGCUCCUGGGGGGUCAGAUAGGCCUGGAGGACUUCAUCUUUGCCCACGUGCGAGGCGAGACCAAGGAGGUGGAGGUCACUAAGACAGAGGAUGCUCUGGGGCUGACCAUCACGGACAACGGGGCUGGCUACGCCUUCAUCAAGAGAAUCAAGGAAGGCAGUAUCAUCAACCGGAUCGAGGCAGUGUGCGUGGGUGACAGCAUCGAAGCCAUCAACGACCACUCCAUUGUGGGCUGCCGCCACUACGAGGUGGCCAAGAUGCUCCGGGAGCUGCCCAAGUCCCAGCCCUUCACCCUGCGCCUGGUGCAGCCCAAGAGGGCCUUCGAUAUGAUUGGCCAGAGAAGUCGGUCCAGCAAAUGUCCAGUAGAGGCGAAAGUGACCAGCGGGAGGGAGACCCUGCGGCUUCGUUCUGGGGGGGCUGCCACAGUGGAGGAAGCGCCCAGUGAGUUUGAGGAGGAGGCAUCUCGGAAGGUUGAUGACCUGCUGGAAAGCUACAUGGGCAUUCGGGACCCCGAGCUGGGUAAGGGGCCAGGCGUCCACCAUGGUGGAGACGUCCAAGAAGACAGCGAGCGCCCAGGAGUUUGCACGCUGUUUAGACUCCGUCUUGGGCGAGUUCGCCUUCCCCGACGAGUUUGUGGUGGAAGUGUGGGCCGCCAUCGGCGAGGCCAGAGAGGCCUGUGGCUAGUUUGCCCUGGGGGGGCCCAGCACAGCCCCAGCCCGGAGCCCAGCCCCCUGCCCCGGCCCUGCUCCAGAACCCAGCCCAGAUCGGAGGACAAGUUCCUCUCUAGAACCCAAUCCAAUUUGGAGCCCCAGCCCAACUCCAGAACCCAACCCUUCUCUAGAAUCCAGCCCAGAUCUGAGGCCAAGCUAUGUGCUAGAGCCCAGGCCAGCUCUGAGACCAAGCCCAGCAUUGAGAAUAAGCUCUGUUCUAAAACUCAGGCCAGCCCUGAGACCAAGCCCAGCUCUAGAACUCAGAUGAGCUUUGAGACCAUGCCCAGCACUGAGACCAAGCCCUGUUCUAGAACUCAGGCCUGCUCUGAGGCCAAGCCCAGCUCUAGAACCCAGAUGAGCUCUGAGACCAUGCCCAGCUCUAGAACUCAGAUGGGCUCUGAGACCAUGCCCAGCUCUAGAACUCAGAUGGGCUCUGAGACCGAGCCCAGCUCUAGAACUCAGAUGGGCUCUGAGACCGAGCCCAGCUCUAAAACUCAGAUGGGCUCUGAGACCAUGCCCAGCUCUAGAACUCAGAUGGGCUCUGAGACCGAGCCCAGCUCUAGAACUCAGAUGGGCUCUGAGACCGAGCCCAGCUCUAGAACUCAGAUGGGCUCUGAGACCAUGCCCAGCUCUAGAACUCAGAUGGGCUCCGAGACCAAGCCCAGCUCUAGAACCCAGAUGAGCUCUGAGACCAUGCCCAGCUCUAGAACUCAGAUGAGCUCUGAGACAGAGCCCAGUAUUGAGACCAAGCCCUGUUCUAGAGUCCAGGCCAGCUCCGAGACCAAGCCCAGCUCUAGAACCCAGAUAAGCUCUGAAACCAAGCCCAGCAUAGAGACCAAGCCGUGUUCUAGAAUUCAGGCCACAUCUGAAGCCAAGCCCAGCUCUAGAACUCAGGUCAGCCCUGAGACCAAGCCCAGCUCUAGAACCCAGAUAAGCUCUGAAACCAAUCCCAGCAUUGAGACCAAGCCCUGUUCUAGAACUCAGGCCACCUCUGAGGCCAAACCCAGCUCUAGAACCCAGAUAAGAUCUGAGACCAAGCCCUGCUCUGAAGCCCAGGCCAGCUCUGAGACGAAGCACAUCUCUAGAAUCCAGCUGAGCCCUGACAACAAGCCAAACUCUGGAACCCAGACACAUUUUAAGACCCAGACCAGCUUGGAGACCAAUCCCAGUUCCAGAAUCCAGGCUAGCUCGGAGACCAAGCCCUGCUGGAAAACUCAAGCUGACUCUGGAACUCUGGACAGCUCCACGAUGCAGCCACACCUGGACACUCGGUCUAGCUCCGGAACCCCAGUUAAUUUUGGAACCCAUGUGAGAUUCAUGAAGCAGCCCAGCUCUGGAACCCCAGUCAGCUCAGGAUUCAGAGACAGCUCCCAAAUCAAAUCCUAUUCAAGAACUCAGACCAGCUCAGAAACCCAGGUCCACACGGCUGCCCAGUCCAGAUCCCAACCCCAGUUGCAUCCAAGUGCCCAUCCCCAUCCUGCAGCCCAGUCCAGCUCCAGUGAUGAUUCCAGCUCUGAGACUGAGCCCAGCUCUAGAACCUCGCCUAGUGCUACAACCAGGCCCAACUCCAGGAUUCAGACCAGCUCUGGAACCCCAUCCAUCUUGGAAGCAAGACCCAGCUCCAGCACACAGCUUGGUGCCAAGCCCCACUCUCCUUGCACAAUGCAGCUCAGCUCUAGAAUGCAGUUUACUUCCAGGACCCAGACCAAUUUCAAGGCCUGGCCAAGCUCCAGAGCUCAAUCCAGCCCAAGCACCGCACCCAGCUCUGGAACUCAGCUCAGUUCUGGAGCACAGGCUGGUUCUGAAAUCCCAGCCAGCUCCAAAACACAGACAGCAGCUGAGACCCAGCCAAGUUCCAGAAUCCAGCUAAGCUCUGGAGUCCAAUCUAGUCCUGGGACCCAGGCCAUCGCAGCAAUAGAAUUAAGCUCCACAGCCCUGUCUAGUUCCGACAGCAGGUCCAGCUCCAGGACCCAGCGCUGCCCAGGAGCUCGACCAGCCUCUGGGACUCAAUUCGCCUCUAAAACCCUGCCAGGUUCUAGAUACCAGCUCCAGACCACAGCCCCAGACAGCUCUGGUAUUCAACUGGACUUUGGGAAGCAGAGCAGUUCUGAAAGUCAGCUUAGCUUUGGAACUCAGCCCAGCUCUGGGACCCAGAUAAGCUCAAGAAUUCAAGCCAGCUCUGGAAGUCAGCUUAGUUCGGGAACCCAGCUGAUUUCCGGAGCCCAACCCAGCUCCAGAACUCAGACUAGUUCUGGAAACCAGCUCAGCUCCGGGACCCAGACCACUGCAAGAAUUCAGCUCAGCCCUGGAGCUCAUCUUAGCUCCAGAACCCAGUCCAGUCCUGAGACCAGGCUCAGCUCUGAGGCUCAGUCCAGCUCUGGAACCCAGUUCAGUUCUGGGAUUCAGUUUGGCUCUGAAACCCAGACCGGCUCAAGAAUUCAGCCCGACUCUGGAGCCCAACUUAGUUCCAGAACCCAGUCCAGCUCUGAGACCGGGCUCAGCUCUGAAACCCAGACCGGCUCAAGAAUUCAGCCCAGCCCUGGAGCCCACCUUAGUUCUGGAACCCAGCCUGUUUCUGGAACCCAAUCCAGUUCCAGAACUCACACCAGUUCAAGAAUCUGGCUGAGCCCUGGAAAUGGAAUCUGCCCACAGACCCCUGGCCUUGACCCUAGAAUCCAGCUUGAGGCCCCUGCCCCAGCCCAACCUCAGCCCCCAGGCCCAUCCCCCAGAGACCCCACCCCAGCCCCUAGCAAAGACCCCCAGCCUCUGCCUCAGCCCCAUGAUCAGGUAUGUGGCAUCCAGGCCAGCCUUGGCCCCAUCCCAGGCUUACCCCAAGCCUCCUACCUGGCCCCACAGUCACAGGUCUCCUCAACCCCCCAGAAGCCAGCCGUCUCUCCCAAGCCCCGGGUGGGACCCCAGAAGUCCACCCCACCCACCAUAUCUGUCACUCCUAGUCCUGCCCCUAGGGCAGCCCUCCUGAGUUCCCAGCUGUCUGAGUCCCCAGCUUUGGCGCCAGCCCUUUGCCCCACUCUGGGGGAGCCAGGAGCCCGCCCUUACCGCGGGGGGCCGUAGCUUGGCUGUGACUUAGCCCUGGUUCAUGUGGUUCUCGUCCUCUCCUGUCCCUUCCAGCCUGGGGCCCCCAGAAGCAGCAAGUGACCUUAUUUCUCCAGCAGGCGGUGGUAGGGAGUGUGCGGUGGUGAAAACAGGGGCUUCACCGGUCCUGGCUCAGAUCCAGGUCCUUGGAGGGAAAAGGAGGGCAGGAGACGGGUUGCACCGCAUGUACCCUGAGGGCUCAUGGUGAAUAAAGGCACCUUCCAUCUCUGCA